AGGUCUGGAGCCAGAGAAGAUGAUCUGAAAUUGUAGCAGGAGAAAUUGAGUGUGGAAUCUAUAUGACCCUGGGAGGGAUGUUGGUUGGAAGAAUGACCAGCUGAUGGAGAUGCUGCUGUAAUUAUUGGUGGUAAUAAUGGGCAGCAGUGAGCCACCCGGUGUGACAGUGUAGGAGAAAACAGUCCAAACUCCUGCCAAACUCUCUCUACUGAUGGCAAAUCAGAGGAGACUCAAAUUGUAAGUUUAUAGUGGUCUGGCUUUUGGCCAUGACAAUGACACCUUGCCCUUUUAAUUUGGGGCCCGUGCAAAUAUUCACUGAAAGCUGUCAAGAGGAAAACAGAAUUGGUUAUUGAAUCACUUGCUUCCUCUAGGUGUAUGAAAAAUAAUUUCAAGUUUAACAAACACAAGGAAACCGCAGGGUCCAUGUCAAAGCUGAUGAGCUAUUUCUGAAACUCGUGCAGAAUUGUGGUUUGUGUGGUCUAUGUCACGGCACCCUUGAGGGAGAGUGGGCAAUUGCCUGAACUUGGAGGCUGUGUCCUGUCCCCAGGCUGCUCCAGGGCUGCCUCCUUCCGACUGGGCCUUCUUAUCUGGGACUGUUGAGGGCAACAGGCCUUCCGAAGACCAGUGAAGAAGGAGGCCCUGCAAACAGGAGGCUGACAGGGUAGGAACGAGGCCAUGAUCCCUUUGCAGAAGGACAACCAGGAGGAGGGUGUCUGCCCCAUCUGCCAGGAGAGCCUGAAGGAGGCCGUGAGCACCAACUGCGGACAUCUCUUCUGUCGAGUGUGCCUGACACAGCAUGUGGAGAAGGCCUCAGCCUCUGGGGUCUUCUGCUGCCCCCUCUGCCGGAAGCCCUGUUCUGAGGAGGUGCUAGGGACAGGCUAUAUCUGCCCCAACCACCAGAAGAGGGUGUGCAGGUUCUGUGAGGAGAGCAGACUUCUUCUAUGUGUGGAAUGCCUGGUGUCCCCUGAACACAUGUCUCAUCAUGAACUGACCAUUGAAAAUGCCCUCAGCCACUACAAGGAACGACUCAAUCGCCGGAGCAGGAAGCUCAGAAAGGACAUUGCAGAACUUCAGCGGCUCAAGGCUCAGCAGGAGAAGAAACUGCAGGCUCUGCAGUUUCAGGUAGACCACGGGAACCACAGGCUGGAGGCUGGGCCGGAGAGCCAGCACCAAACCAGGGAACAGCUGGGUGCCCUCCCUCAGCAGUGGCUGGGCCAGCUGGAGCACAUGCCAGCAGAAGCGGCCAGAAUCCUUGACAUCUCCAGGGCAGUAACACAGCUCAGAAGCCUGGUCAUUGAUCUGGAAAGGACGGCCAAGGAAUUAGACACCAACACACUGAAGGAGUGCUCCACAGAAAUUAGAGGUUAUUUAUCCCCAGUUGGAGAAAGGAGUCAGUGAAUUGCUUCUUCAGCCCCCUCAGAAGCUCUGACCUGUUCAUCCCUGGGACACCUCACUUCAGGCUCACCUCAGCCUCCUCUCUCUCCUUCCUCCAACCUGUCCAGGCCCCCACUGGGUCUACCCAGUGCAUCUUCGGGCCUGCCAGCUCCUGAACAUGUCACCAUUUCUUCAUGUCCACAGUCAUCACCUGAUGCCUGACCCUCUGACUCUUGGACGAUAGCCAGCCUCCUUCCAGGACAGGCUCAUGCUUGGGGCUGCCACUGUGGAGGUCGGGGCCCAUGGUCUCCAGGAGCAUUUGUGAAAUCUCCAUUUUGCCUGUAAACUGAUGGUAGUGCCCAUCUCUCACAAUCUCAUUCAAAUAGGAUCCUCCAGGCCUCUGAAUGGCCCGAGCUCAUCAGCAGUGACACCACCUCACAUGUGGAGCCCAGCUGAGUUCCUGCAGUACUUGUUGUCUGUACCACUCACCUGGCACUUAUUUAUUAUUGUUGUGGAAGACAGACUCAAAGACAGCCUCCCUUCAUGAUCCUCACCUCUUGGAAUUCAUGCCCUUGUUUGGUCCCCUCCCCUUGAGUGUAAGUGGGAUCUGUGACUUGCUUCUAAUGAAUGGAAUAAGGCAAAGGUGAUAGGGUGUCACUCUGGCAACUGUGUUGCAUUGUAUAGAACUCCUCCUUGCUGGCCCACCCUUUUAGAGCCCCUCCUAGGAGCCAAGAGCAGCUUCCAGCCAACAACAAGCAGAGGCCCUCAGUCUUGUGGCUGCAAGAACCUGAAUUCUGCCAACAACCCGAGUGAGCUUGGAAGCAGAUUCUUCCCCAACUGAGCCGGAUAAGAACCUAGUCCAGCCAACACCUUGAUUAUAGUCUUGUGAGUACCUAAGCUGAGGACCCAGUGAAGCUGUGCCAAAAUUUCCCACCCACAGAAACAGUGUGACAAUAAAUGUGUGUGUGUUU